AAUUCUUCAUUAUGCAGAGGACUUGACAAGUUGUUUUCCAGAGAGGCCGUUCGUAGUUAUGUCACACUACUUCUACUUGACUCCACAAAUUCUUCUGCCCUUUAGCCCUCUUACUUCUCAAGAGUUUGAUCUGAUCAGACGCAAGGCUGGAGCAUCUUGGCAGGAUGAAACACGAUGGUCAGAUUCUUCCGUGACAACAUACACAGGCAGUUACCGGAAAAAACAACUGGACAAGUCCAUGUGCAGCCAAUUUUCUUUUAGAGCAGGACAGCAUGAGCCUGAGUGUAAACAGAUGUCAUUGACAAACAGUUCUGCCUGUCAUCUUCUCUGCUGGGCUGGUACCCAAGAGACUACAGAUAUCAAAGGACUAUUCCCUGAUAUAACCAGGCCCUUUAAAAAGUCAUUUGAUGUCAAGCAUGGAGUGGCACAUCAAAUUUGGGAUUUUGGUGAUUGUUUUCCGACACCUCCAAAUUAUGGAAAAUACUGUGUGAGACCUAAAAAGCCAGCACAGGAGGCCCUGAUAAACUACAGUCGACGAGGGAAAGGUGUCCUAAAGCAUCUUCAUGGACGGUGCGAUUCUGAAAGCAAGGUUUGCUCAUCUGAGGAUUCAGAAGCUGAUCGAUACUCCGAUUAUGGCUGGGGAGGACCCUCAUCGCCAUUUAACUGAGUUGGAAAAUGAAGCCACAAGGCUGGAGGCGUGGAGUUUGCUUAAUAAACAACUUUGAGGUGGAAUAUAAGCCUCGAGUUUUAGCUGUAUGUGUUUCCUUAUGGUAAGUGGUUAGCUUUUAUUUCCUUCAUUGUGAAUUGACUGCUCAUGUCCUCAUAUCCUUUGCUAAUUCUUCAAUUAGAGGCCUAAAGGUUUUCUUAACAGUUUAUAGGAAUACUCUAUGUAGUAAAUAUAUUAACCUUUUGUCAUUUUUGUAAACACAUUUUUUCAGACCCAGGUUUUGGUUUUGCUUCUCUUUUUCUGUUAUUUUGCAAACUGAAGAAAUUUUUAUGUGUCAGAUCUCUCGAUUGUUUUCAUUUGUGCUUUAUUUUAUCACUUAAGCUUUUACAAAUCCUUCUAGCUCUGGAAGCUUGAUAAAUAUUCUAUUUUCUUCAGGCUUUUCUAGGGCUGAUUUGUUAAUAGGGAUUCUGUAAGUUAUCUGGAAUUUAUUUUGGUGUCAAUGUGAGGUGAGGUAUUGAUAGUUGUAUUUUCCAAAUAGCCAUUCAGAUUCCUCAAUGCCAUUUAUUGCAACAUUUAGAAAUUGCAGCAAAAUUUGCACUGAAGAAGUCACAAGCACCAAAGGGGAUAUUUUCCCCUUGUUGAUAUUCUCUGCAGGGACAAGACGCCAGACAGUGGGAGAAAGAAGGUGAGGAGGGAUCACUAAGCGGAAAUGCCUAAUGAGAGGACAGUUCCUCAGGUAUCCCUUUAACAUAACCACUCACAGGCAUGCCUGGAGUAACACCAACCCAUAAGAAAAUGUGAGAAAGCAUGGGUUCUGUAGGAGACUAAACAAAAUGCGUGCUGUUGAUUAGAGCUUAUCCUGUAGAUCACAACUUCACUUAGGUAACAAGAUAGCGUGGCAGAUUUCCUAAGGUACUGAAAUAAUAGGGGCCUUUUCCUAAGACAGGAAAAUCAAAUUAGAGAACAAGGCUCAUAAAAUUAGAGAAUCUUAGGCCUAAGGGCAUCUUCUGCGCAUCUGAAAAUAUAGGGAACAGAUGGAGGUCCAGAGAAGUUAACUGAGGUCCUACAUUCACAAUACUACUUAUGGUACCAUAGGGUCUAGAACCUGGAUCGAGAAUUCAGUGUGUGCUUUCCUCCAUGCCAAGUAACUUCCACAUAGAUUACAGAAAUAAGUCACUAGGACUCUAAGGUUCAAGCAAGGGCCACAUCUGAAUAGUUUUCUUACUUAGCAUGCACAAAUGUGCACAGAUGAGCUUGCACACAAAUAUAUUCAUUCACUGAAGGUACAUUGAUUCCCCACUUGUACUGUGUAGGGCCUGCUCCAGGUGCUGAGAUACAGCAGUGACUUAGAUAAGCUCCCUGUUCUUGGGAAUAUAUACUGCUAUAUAUGUCAUAUAACAUAUAUAUUGCUUUAUACCCUAACUUUGCAAUAGUCCAACUUACUAAUUUACAGAUUUAGAUUGAUCUAUUUUGGGUCAAACUGAAACAUCUCAAAACUAUACUAAAUACAGGAAACCCUUGCUGUGAGACCAUUAGCUUAUAAUGGGGGUCAGCAAACUACAGUCCUUGGGCUCAAAUGAGCCUCCUGUUUUUAUAAAUAAAGUUUUAUUGGAACAUGGCCAUGCCCACUCAUUUGCAUAUUGUCUACGACUACUUUCAAGUUUCAACAGCCGAGUUGAGUAGUAGUGACAGAAACUGUAUGACCUGAAAGCCUAAAAUAUUUACUAUUUGCCCCUUUGAAAAAAGCUUGCAGGACCCUGGCUUAUAAAAUAGGUUUUAACCUUAUUCUUAGAGCAGCAGCAUUAAAGGCUCCUACUGAAUUAAAAAAGAAACUUCUUUAAUGCAUUUCACUCUUGGGUGACUGUACUAACAAACAAGAAUAUUCUUUCCUGCUAGACAAUGAGCCCUGAAUCCUGCUACAUCAGAGAGAACAAGAUCUUUGCUUCAUUCCCUGUGGUAAUUACGAGGUUAGAAAGAACUCACCAGCGAAAAUUUCUGGACCUGAUGCCUUUAUAAACGGUGGCAAGUGCUGCUGCAUUUCAUGGCCUCAGAUCAAAAUACAACCUCAUUAGCUGCUGUGAACACAACGUUCCUGUUGAAGAAUAGAAUGGAAUGGAGUUAAGAGUGUAGAAGGUCUGAUGCAAAUUUACUCCUACUCCUAUUGACAAAGAGUUUGAACUACUGAAUUUGUAUAUGAAAGUCAGGGCAUCCUAUUGUUUUCAGUUGUCAUAAGAAAAAAAAAAAGAAAAAAAAGAAAUGGCAUUACUACUGUCAAUAUAAAUAAAUGAAAAAUCUAAGCUA